AGUUUGCAGCGCCUGCGCCGGGUGCGCCAACUACGCAAAGACCAAGCGGGCUCCGCGCGGACCGGCCGCGGGGCUAGGGACCCGGCUUUGGCCUUCAGGCUCCCUAGCAGCGGGGAAAAGGAAUUGCUGCCCGGAGUUUCUGCGGAGGUGGAGGGAGAUCAGGAAACGGCUUCUUCCUCACUUCGCCGCCUGGUGAGUGUCGGGGAGAUUGGCAAACGCCUAGGAAAGGACUGGGGAAAAUAGCCCUGGGAAAGUGGAGAAGGUGAUCAGGAGGCCGGUCCACUACGGCAGUUUAUCUGUCUGAUCAGAGCCAGACGCGACGCGUCCACUUCGCAGUUCUUUCCAGGUGUGGGGACCGCAGGACAGACGGCCGAUCCCGCCGCCCUCCGUACCAGCACUCCCAGGAGAGUCAGCCUCGCUCCCCAACGUCGAGGGCGCUCUGGCCACGAAAAGUUCCUGUCCACUGUGAUUCUCAAUUCCUUGCUUGGUUUUUUUCUCCAGAGAACUUUUGGGUGGAGAUAUUAACUUUUUUCUUUUUUUUUUCCUUGGUGGAAGCUGCUCUAGGGAGGGGGGAGGAGGAGGAGAAAGUGAAAUGUGCUGGAGAAGAGCGAGCCCUCCUUGUUCUUCCGGAGUCCCAUCCAUUAAGCCAUCACUUCUGGAAGAUUAAAGUUGUCGGACAUGGUGACAGCUGAGAGGAGAGGAGGAUUUCUUGCCAGGUGGAGAGUCUUCACCGUCUGUUGGGUGCAUGUGUGCGCCCGCAGCGGCGCGGGGCGCGUGGUUCUCCGCGUGGAGUCUCACCUGGGACCUGAGUGAAUGGCUCCCAGGGGCUGUGCGGGGCAUCCGCCUCCGCCUUCUCCACAGGCCUGUGUCUGUCCUGGAAAGAUGCUAGCAAUGGGGGCGCUGGCAGGAUUCUGGAUCCUCUGCCUCCUCACUUAUGGUUACCUGUCCUGGGGCCAGGCCUUAGAAGAGGAGGAAGAAGGGGCCUUACUAGCUCAAGCUGGAGAGAAACUAGAGCCCAGCACAACUUCCACCUCCCAGCCCCAUCUCAUUUUCAUCCUAGCGGAUGAUCAGGGAUUUAGAGAUGUGGGUUACCACGGAUCUGAGAUUAAAACACCUACUCUUGACAAGCUCGCUGCCGAAGGAGUUAAACUGGAGAACUACUAUGUCCAGCCUAUUUGCACACCAUCCAGGAGUCAGUUUAUUACUGGAAAGGUCCUGCUGUGUCGCCCAGGCUGGAGUGCAGCGGCAUAAUCAUGGCUCACUGCAGCCUCAACCUCCCAGGCUCAAGUCAUCCUCCUGCUUCAGCCUCCCAAGUACCUAGGACUACAGACAUCCUGUUAUUUGAUCUUCACAUUCACGCUGAAGAUGAGGAAACUGAGGAUCAGAGGGAUUAAGUACUUCCCAAAACCAUACAGGUAUCAGAUACACACCGGACUUCAACAUUCUAUCAUAAGACCUACCCAACCCAACUGUUUACCUCUGGACAAUGCCACCCUACCUCAGAAACUGAAGGAGGUUGGAUAUUCAACGCAUAUGGUCGGAAAAUGGCACUUGGGUUUUUACAGAAAAGAAUGCAUGCCCACCAGAAGAGGAUUUGAUACCUUUUUUGGUUCCCUUUUGGGAAGUGGGGAUUACUAUACACACUACAAAUGUGACAGUCCUGGGAUGUGUGGCUAUGACUUGUAUGAAAACGACAAUGCUGCCUGGGACUAUGACAAUGGCAUAUACUCCACACAGAUGUACACUCAGAGAGUACAGCAAAUCUUAGCUUCCCAUAACCCCACAAAGCCUAUAUUUUUAUAUAUUGCCUAUCAAGCUGUUCAUUCACCACUGCAAGCUCCUGGCAGGUAUUUCGAACACUACCGAUCCAUUAUCAACAUAAACAGGAGGAGAUAUGCUGCCAUGCUUUCCUGCUUAGAUGAAGCAAUCAACAACGUGACAUUGGCUCUAAAGACUUAUGGUUUCUAUAACAACAGCAUUAUCAUUUACUCUUCAGAUAAUGGUGGCCAGCCUACGGCAGGAGGGAGUAACUGGCCUCUCAGAGGUAGCAAAGGAACAUAUUGGGAAGGAGGGAUCCGGGCUGUAGGCUUUGUGCAUAGCCCACUUCUGAAAAACAAGGGAACAGUGUGUAAGGAACUUGUGCACAUCACUGACUGGUACCCCACUCUCAUUUCACUGGCUGAAGGACAGAUUGAUGAGGACAUUCAACUAGAUGGCUAUGAUAUCUGGGAGACCAUAAGUGAGGGUCUUCGCUCACCCCGAGUAGAUAUUUUGCAUAACAUUGACCCCAUAUACACCAAGGCAAAAAAUGGCUCCUGGGCAGCAGGCUAUGGGAUCUGGAACACUGCAAUCCAGUCAGCCAUCAGAGUGCAGCACUGGAAAUUGCUUACAGGAAAUCCUGGCUACAGCGACUGGGUCCCCCCUCAGUCUUUCAGCAACCUGGGACCGAACCGGUGGCACAAUGAACGGAUCACCUUGUCAACUGGCAAAAGUGUAUGGCUUUUCAACAUCACAGCCGACCCAUAUGAGAGGGUGGACCUAUCUAACAGGUAUCCAGGAAUCGUGAAGAAGCUCCUACGGAGGCUCUCACAGUUCAACAAAACUGCAGUGCCGGUCAGGUAUCCCCCCAAAGACCCCAGAAGUAACCCUAGGCUCAAUGGAGGGGUCUGGGGACCAUGGUAUAAAGAGGAAACCAAGAAAAAGAAGCCAAGCAAAAAUCAGGCUGAGAAAAAGCAAAAGAAAAGCAAAAAAAAGAAGAAGAAACAGCAGAAAGCAGUCUCAGGUUCAACUUGCCAUUCAGGUGUUACUUGUGGAUAAGCACAAAUAUUUCCUGUUUGGUUAAACUUUAAUCAGUUCUUAUCUUUCAUCUGUUUCCUAGGUAAACCAGCAAAUUUGGCUCGAUAAUAUCGCUGGCCUAAGCGUCAGGCUUGUUUUCAUGCUGUGCCACUCCAGAGACUUCUGCCACCUGGCCGCCACACUGAAAACUGUCCUGCUCAGUGCCAAGGUGCUACUCUUGCAAGCCACACUUAGAGAGAGUGGAGAUGUUUAUUUCUCUUGCUCCUUUAGAAAACGUGGUGAGUCCUGAGUUCCACUGCUGUGCUUCAGUCAACUGACCAAACACUGCUUUGAAUUAUAGGAGGAGAACAAUAACCUACCAUCCGCAAGCAUGCUAAUUUGAUGGAAGUUACAGGGUAUACCAUCCGCAAGCAUGCUAAUUUGAUGGAAGUUACAGGGUAGCAUGAUUAAAACUACCUUUGAUAAAUUACAGUCAAAGAUUGUGUCACCUCAAAGGCCUUGAAGAAUAUAUUUUCUUGGUGAAUUUUUGUAUGUCUGUCAUAUGACACUUGGGUUUUUUAAUUAAUUCUAUUUUAUAUAUAUAUAUAUGUUUCUUUUCCUGUGAAAAGCUGUUUUUCUCACAUGUGAACAGCUUGCACCUCAUUUUACCAUGCGUGAGGGAAUGGCAAAUAAGAAUGUUUGAGCACACUGCCCACAAUGAAUGUAACUAUUUUCUAAACACUUUACUAGAAGAACAUUUCAGUAUAAAAAACCUAAUUUAUUUUUACAGAAAAAUAUUUUGUUGUUUUUAUAAAAAGUUAUGCAAAUGACUUUAUUUUAUUUUUAUUUCCUGCAUACCAUUAGAAUAAUUUUAUUUCAUUUCUUCAAAUUACCAAGCACUGUAAUACUAUAAAUUAAUGUAAUACUGUGUGAAUUCAGACUAUAAAAAACAUCAUUCAGAAAACUUUAUAAUCGUCAUUGUUCAACCAAGAUUUUGAAUGUAAUAAGAUGAAUAUAUUCCUUACAAAUUACUUGGAAAUUCAAUGUUUGUGCAGAGUUGAGACAACUUUAUUGUUUCUAUCAUAAACUAUUUAUGUAUCUUAAUUAUUAAAAUGAUUUACUUUAUGGCACUAGAAAAUUUACUGUGGCUUUUCUGAUCUAACUUCUAGCUAAAAUUGUAUCAUUGGUCCUAAAAAAUAAAAAUCUUUACUAAUAGGCAAUUGAAGGAAUGGUUUGCUAACAACCACAGUAAUAUAAUAUGAUUUUACAGAUAGAUGCUUCCCCUUGGCUAUGACAUGGAGAAAGAUUUUCCCAUAAUAAUAACUAACAUUUAUAUUAGGUUGGUGCAAAACUAGUUGCGGUUUUUCCCAUUAAAAGUAAUAAACUUACUCUUAUACAAAGUGGACACUGUGGGGAGAUACAGAGAAAUGGAAGAUACGGAUCCUGCCUGGAGUAGGUAACCUUGCUUGGAAACCCCACAUGCAAACGUCAUGAGGAGAAUUAAAGGAGUAUUAUCAGUAAUGAAGUUUAUCAUGGGUCAUCAAUGAGCAUAGAUUGGUGUGGAUCCUGUAGACCCUGGUGUUUUCUUUGAAGUGCCCUCUCCUAAUGCAGAGGCCUUGAAGCUUACAGUAUACACUUGAAAAGUCACAGAUAGCUAGAAUUAUGAUCUUUGAAGUUAUAACUGUGAUCUGAAAAUGUGUGUGGUGGUAUGACAGCAUACCAUUAAAUACAUUUACAUCACAGCUCAAAGGACUGUGAUAUAAUCCAUUUAUAUCACAACUCAAAGGACUGUGAUAUAAUCCAUUUAUAUCACAGCUCACAGUUUCUGAAAAUGUAUAAAAGAAUCUAUAAUCUAGUACUGAAAUUACUAAAUUGGGUAAGAUGAUUUAAAUGAUUUUAAUUUUAACAUUUUAUUUCUAGAAUAUAUGGCUCCAUUUUAUUUUAUAGUGUAAAGUUGUAUUUCCUAAAGUUUGUGUUUUGUCGACAGUAUCUUUUAAAUGAGUCUUAAAAAUAAAGGCAUAUUGUUCAUGUU